GCUCGGGCCUUCCCGGCGUCUCCGCGCAGGCCUCGGGGAAGCGGGGUCCGGGGGAGCCGUGGUGCGGUGGGACCGCGUGGGUCCUGGAAGAGCUGCAGAGGAGAGUGACGGCUUUGGAUGCGCUUUGCCCCAGGGCCUUUCUUCCCGGAGUUGGCCUUUUCCCUGCCCUUCUCUUCUCCUGGCGUGGUGACCUGCCUCCCUUCUCCUGGAUCGCUUUGCUGGCAGCCACCUUGUAACACCUCAGACCCUUCAGAGACUUCCUGUUGCUCUGAGGACACUCAUCCCAGCCGACCAGGCCCACCAGGCCCCCAACAGCACUACCUGGCUGGGGUCACGUGCAGGUCUCCUGGCUCUGGCAGGUGGGAGAAGGAGAAGCACGAAGACGGGGUGAAGUGGAGACAGCUGGAGCACAAGGGCCCGUACUUCGCACCCCCAUACGAGCCCCUUCCCGACGGAGUGCGUUUCUUCUAUGAAGGAAGGCCUGUGAGAUUGAGCGUGGCAGCGGAGGAGGUCGCCACUUUUUAUGGGAGGAUGUUAGAUCAUGAAUACACAACAAAGGAGGUUUUCCGGAAGAACUUCUUCAAUGACUGGCGAAAGGAAAUGGCGGUGGAAGAGAGGGAAGUCAUCAAGAGCCUGGACAAGUGUGACUUCACGGAGAUCCACAGAUACUUUGUGGACAAGGCCGCAGCCCGGAAAGUCCUGAGCAGGGAGGAGAAGCAGAAGCUAAAAGAAGAGGCAGAAAAACUUCAGCAAGAGUUCGGCUACUGUAUUUUAGAUGGUCACCAAGAAAAAAUAGGCAACUUCAAGAUUGAGCCGCCUGGCUUGUUCCGUGGCCGUGGCGACCAUCCCAAGAUGGGGAUGCUGAAGAGAAGGAUCACGCCAGAGGAUGUGGUUAUCAACUGCAGCAGGGACUCGAAGAUCCCCGAGCCGCCGGCGGGGCACCAGUGGAAGGAGGUGCGCUCCGAUAACACCGUCACGUGGCUGGCAGCUUGGACCGAGAGCGUUCAGAACUCCAUCAAGUACAUCAUGCUGAACCCUUGCUCGAAGCUGAAGGGGGAGACAGCUUGGCAGAAGUUUGAAACAGCUCGACGCCUGCGGGGAUUUGUGGACGAGAUCCGCUCCCAGUACCGGGCUGACUGGAAGUCUCGGGAAAUGAAGACGAGACAGCGGGCGGUGGCCCUGUAUUUCAUCGAUAAGCUGGCACUGAGAGCAGGAAAUGAGAAGGAGGACGGUGAGGCGGCCGACACCGUGGGCUGCUGUUCCCUCCGCGUGGAGCACGUCCAGCUGCACCCGGAGGCCGAUGGCUGCCAACACGUGGUGGAAUUUGACUUCCUGGGGAAGGACUGCAUCCGCUACUACAACAGAGUGCCGGUGGAGAAGCCGGUGUACAAGAACUUACAGCUCUUUAUGGAGAACAAGGACCCCCGGGACGACCUCUUCGACAGGCUGACCACGACCAGCCUGAACAAGCACCUCCAGGAGCUGAUGGACGGGCUGACGGCCAAGGUGUUCCGGACCUACAACGCCUCCAUCACUCUGCAGGAGCAGCUGCGGGCCCUGACGCGCGCCGAGGACAGCAUAGCAGCUAAGAUCUUAUCCUACAACCGAGCCAACCGAGUCGUGGCCAUUCUCUGCAACCAUCAGCGAGCAACCCCCAGUACGUUCGAGAAGUCGAUGCAGAAUCUCCAGACGAAGAUCCAGGCAAAGAAGGAGCAGGUGGCUGAGGCCAGGGCAGAGCUGAGGAGGGCGAGGGCUGAGCACAAAGCCCAAGGGGAUGGCAAGUCCAGGAGCUCGUGCCCUCAGUCUCUUGCCUCAGCACCUAGGUAGCUGCCGCCCACACCAACCCAGAUGUGGCAGCUUCAGACGCGCCUUCCCAUGGCCAGUUUUGUUUUCCUCUUCAAUUGUUAUUUUGUGAUUUUUUUUUUUUUUUUUUUGAGAUGGAGUCUCUGUCGCCAGGCUGGAGUGCGCUGGCGCGGUCUCAGCUCACUGCAACCUCCGCCUCCCGGGUUCAAGUGAUUCUCCUGCCUCAGCCUCCCGAGUAGCUGGGGUUACAGGUGCGCGCCACCACGCCCGGCUCAUUUAUUUAUUUAGUAGAAACGGGGUUUCUCCAUGUUGGCCAGGCUGGUCAAACUCCUGGCCUCAAGUGAUCCUCCUGCCUUGGCAUCUCAAAGUGCUGGGAUUACAGGCAUGAGCCACUGCACCUGGCCAACUUUGUGAUUUUUAAAAAUACAAACUAUAUGCCUUGUGGACAAGAGUGGGACACAUGGAGCCGUGGGAGGAGGAGACCCUGGCCGCCAAGGAGGUUUGUGAUUGUCAUUGUGGGGUCAGGAAAUGAGAAGAAGGUGCCAGACUCUUCUCCAGGGCGGCGGCACCAUCCCCUCCCCACCAGCAGUGUGUGAGGGCUCCGAUUCCUCUGUCCAGGCGCCACUGUAGGGUCAGUUUUCCAUGUGUCGAUUAGAGCCCAGUGGGUGUGAAGGAGCGUCUGGCCGUGGGUGCUCUUUGCAGGUGCUUGUUGCCCACUUCUGUAUCGUCUCUGGAGAAUGACUGCUCAGGUCCUCUGUCCAUUUUCCAGUCGGGUUGUUGUUUUAUUAUUGACUUGUAAGAGCUCGUCGAUGUUUCGCCCACUCUUGGGUUGUCUUUGUUCUUUCUUUUUUUUUUUUUUCCUUUGGAGACAGAGCAUUGCUCUGUCGCCAAGGCUGGAGUGCAAUGGCAUGAUCUCGGCUCACUGCAAUCUCUGCCUCCAGGUUUCAAGCAAUUCUCCUGCCUCAGCCUCCUGAGUAGCUGGGAUUACAGGCACCCGCCACCAUGCCCGGCUAAUUUUUUUGUAUUUUAGUAGAGACGGGGUUUCACCAUGUUGCCCAGGCUGGUCUUGAACUCCUGAGCUCAGGCAAUCUGCCUGUCUCGGCCUCCCAAAGUGCUGGGAUUACAGGUGUGAGUCACUACUCCCAGCCCUAUUUUUUUUUUUUUUUUUUGGUGAUGGAGUCUUGCUCUGUCACCCAGGCUAGAGUGCAGUGGCGUGAUCUUGGCUUACUGCAACCUCUGCCUCCUGGGUUCAAGCGAUUCUCCUGCCUCAGCCUCCCGAGUAGCUGAGACUACAGACACACACCACUAUACCUGGCUAAUUUUUGUAUUUUAGUACAGAUGGGGUUUCACCAUGUCGGUCAGGCUGGUCUUGAACUCCUGACCUCGGGUGAUCCACCCACCUCGGCCUCCCAAAGUGCUGGGAUUACAGGUGUGAGCAACUGCGCCCGGCCACAUCUUUCUUCUUUCUUGUUGGUGUCCUGUGACACAUUUAAGAUUUGGAUGAGUCAGCGUGCUGAGAAGGCUUUGCCUAACCCAAGGCCAUGAAGAUAGAUUUCUCUGUUUUCUCCUAAGAGGUUUAUUGGUUUACUCUUACAUUUAGGUCAUUGGUUCUGAGUUAAUUUUUGUGUGUGGUCUGAGGGAAGGGCCCAGGGUCAUUCUCUUGCAUGUGGACAGCCAGAUGUCUCAGCAUCCUAGCUCACCAUAGUCUCAACUUGCUGGGCUCAAGCAAUCCUCCCGCCUCAGCCUCCUGAGUAGCUGGGACCACAGGUGCCAACGGCCACAACUGGCUAAUUUUUACACUAAGAAAAUUUUUGUAUGUUGCCCAAGCUACUCUUGAACUCCUGGCUUUAAGCAAUCCUGCCUUGGCCUCCCAGAGCUCUGAGAUUAAAAGUAUGAGCCAACAUGCCUGGCCCUUAGGACUGUAUCUAUAAAGGCCAUAUUGUAUGCAAACAGAGAUAGUUUUACUUUUUCUUUUCCAAUCAUAUGCCUUUUAUUUCAUAUUUUUGCAUUAUGGACCUGGCAGGAAUCUCCAGUACACUGGACAUGAGUGGGCAGCCUUGCCUUGUUCCUGAUACUGGGGGCAAAACUCUCAUGCUUUUAUCAUGGAAUAUGAUGUUAACUGUAGGUUUUUCACAGAAGCUGUUUGUUAAGUUAACAAAAUUUACUUCUAUUCCUAGUUUGUUGAGGUUCUUUUUUUUUUAUCAUGAAGAGCAUUGGAUUUUGUCAAAUGAUUUUCUGCACCUGUUGAGAUCUUGUUUUUGUCCCUUCCUUAUAUUGAUAGGAUGUAUUAUACUAAUUGAUCAGAUAUGAAACCAUCCUUGCAUUCCUGGGAUAAAUCCUACUUGAGCAAUUGUGUAAUCAUUUUUGUCUAUUGCUGGAUUCAGUUUGCUGAUAUUUUGUUGAGGUUUUUGCAUCUGUAUUCAUGAGCAUGUUAGUCUAUAGUUUUCUUAUGAUGUCAUUGAUUUUGGUAUCAAGGUAAUACUGGUAACGAGUUGAAUAAUAUUUAAUAUAAUAUCUAAUAUUUCAUGAAAGUUUAUGAAAAAUUGGUGCCUUUUUAAAGAGAGAGUCUUGCUGUGUUGCUCAGGCUGGUCUUGAACUCCUGGGCUCAAGCAGUCCUCCGAACUCAGCCUCCUGAAUAGCUGAGACUAUAGGCUUGCACUGCACUGCCUGGCUAGGGUCAGUUUGUUAAAUGAAUUCACCAGUGAAACCAUCUAGGCCUGGGCUUUUCUUUGGGAGACGUUUAAAGUUACUGAUAUAAUCACUUGUUAUAGUUCUAUUCAUAUUUUCUAUACUUUGUGAGUUGGUUCUGGUAGUUUGUAUCUUUCUGGGAAUUUGUUUAGUCUAGGGUGUCUAACUGGCUGGUGCCCAGUUAUUCAUAGUAUUCCCAUAUUAUCUUUUUUAUUUCUUUAGUGAUGUUCCCUCUUUCAUUCAUUCCUCAUUAUUGUGGCUGCGGUUCUUUUUUUUUUUUUUUUGACACAGAGUCUCUCACUCUGUUGCCCAGGCUGGAGUGCAGUGGCAUGAUCUCAGCUCACCACAACCUCUGCCUCCCGGGUUCAAACUAUUUUCCUGCCUCAGCCUCCUGAGUAGCUGGGAUUACAGGUGCACGGCACCAUGCCUGGCUAAUUUUUGUAUUUUUAGUAGAGACGGAGUUUCACCAUGUUAGCCAGGAUGGUCUCAAUCUCCUGACCUCGUGAUCCACCCGCCUCGGCCUCCCACAGUGCUGGGAUUACAGGCGUGAGCCACUGCUCCUGGCCUGGCUGUGGUUCUUAAAGGGUAAAAGUUUUCUCUUCAGGAUGAGCAUCCGGAGAUGCAGGGGUCUGUUUUUAAUGGUGGCGUGUGCGAAGGAAAUGUCAAUUGGAACAAAGGGUAUUCAGUGAAAAAUAAGGCUGUGACUCACCCCUGACCUCCUGUCCCCAGAGGCAGCUGCUGUAAAAUUUCUUUAGCAUUUCCUGGCCAGGCAAGGUUGCUCAUGCCUGUAAUCCCAACACUCUGGGCAGCCGAGGCAGGCAGAUCACUUGAGGUUGGGAGUUUGAGACCAUCAUGGCCAACAUGGUGAAACCCUGUCUCUGCUAAAAAUACAAAAAAAAAAAAAAAAAAAAAAAUCAUGUGCGUGGUGGCACAUGCCUGUAGUCCCAGCUACUCAGGAGGCAGGAGAUUCACUUGAACCCGGGAGGCAGAGGUUCCAGUGAGCUGAGAUCAUGCAACUGCACUCCAGCCUGGGUGACAAAGCAAGACUCCGUCUCAAAAAAAAAAAAAAAAAGCCAAGAGAAAUUUCUUAAGCAUUUCCAGAAGGACUGUGUGUGCGUGCUGGCUCUUCCUCUGUUUUCCCUCCUUGUUUUCACAUAAAUAGCAGCCCCUCAUGUGUCCCUCGGCCCCUGGGGAUGUGGCUCAUGCUGGGAAGGCACUUCCCCGGACCUAUGCUUCUGGCCCGGCGGGCUGCCCCAUUCUCAGCCGUAUUUUUGCAGGCGCAAGUUUGUCUUUCCACGCACAUUCGAGUGUUUGUGGCACAAAUUCCUAGAAGAGUUGGGGUCAGAGGUUGCAUGUGUGGGUGAUGUUCUGGCAUUGGAGGGUGCAAGUAAUGUGGAAAGGGCAUCUCUGUGCUGAAAUUUGCUUUCCCUAAGGAGGCAGGAAGGAGGGCUUAGCGGCUUCCCGGAGGUUAAAGGACAUUUGUGUUUGCUUUCUCGGGCCUGGUCUCGCUGCCCUCAUCCUGUUUGGGCCGGCCUCAGUCUGUUGUGUCGAGCAUCUCACCCUCCUGCGAGUCAGGUCCUGACGGGCUGCUCACCCUCCGCCCACGGCCCUCCUCUGUAUCUGACUUGGCAGCUGGGGUGGGGCUGAGCUUCCACCUUUGAUCCCGGCUGGUCUUUUGCUGUGAUGGAUGACUGAUGACAAUGACAGGGACAGGGCUGCACUGGGAGGGAAGGCGGCAGGGCCAGAGAAGUGCAGGUCUCCUCAGGUGGCGCUAGUCCAGCGCGGGGCCUCGCGGCCUCCUCUUCUCU